GUGUUUAACUGGAAACUAGAACGAGAUGGAAGGGGAUGUUCAAGGCCCCUCCCUUGACUCUGAACGGACCCCCAGGGAACAUGCGACCCUCUCUCUGGCGACGCCUCCCACCCACCACUAAUACUUGCUCCUGGACCGGGGGGCGCGGAGGUUGGAGAGAGGAGGCAGGUGUCUGCAUGCUACCCGGGUCUCGGACAGGCGGCACUGGGACCACGAGGCAGGGAGCCAGGCUUGAAGCAGGUGACAUGUAGACGUCCCCUGGUCCAGCCUCGGAACCUGAGCGCCCUUCUGCCUGGAAAGUUUGUGGCUAGGCGCCAUGGCCAAGAGCAGCUCCCUGAAUGUUCGCGUGGUGGAGGGCCGCGCGCUGCCUGCCAAGGACGUGUCUGGGAGCAGCGACCCCUACUGCCUAGUGAAAGUGGACGACGAGGUGGUGGCCAGGACAGCUACUGUCUGGAGGAGCCUGGGCCCCUUCUGGGGGGAGGAGUACACGGUGCACCUGCCUCUGGAUUUCCACCAGCUGGCCUUCUACGUGCUGGAUGAGGACACUGUCGGGCACGACGACAUCAUCGGCAAGAUCUCGCUGAGCAGGGAGGCGAUUACAGCCGACCCCCGAGGGAUUGACAGCUGGAUUAACUUGAGCCGAGUGGACCCAGAUGCAGAAGUGCAGGGUGAGAUCUGCCUGUCAGUGCAGAUGCUGGAGGAUGGGCAGGGCCGCUGCCUUCGCUGCCAUGUGCUUCAGGCCAGGGACCUGGCUCCCAGAGACAUCUCUGGCACAUCUGACCCAUUUGCACGUGUGUUUUGGGGCAGCCAGAGCUUGGAGACCUCAACCAUCAAGAAGACUCGCUUCCCGCACUGGGAUGAAGUGCUGGAGCUGCGGGAGAUGCCAGGUGCCCCGUCCCCACUGCGGGUGGAGCUCUGGGACUGGGACAUGGUGGGCAAGAAUGACUUCUUGGGCAUGGUGGAGUUCUCUCCAAAGACCCUCCAGCAGAAGCCACCUAAAGGCUGGUUCCGCCUCCUGCCCUUUCCCAGAGCCGAGGAGGAUUCUGGGGGGAACCUGGGUGCCCUGCGAGUGAAGGUACGCCUGAUUGAGGACCGCGUCCUGCCCUCCCAGUGCUACCAGCCUCUCAUGGAGCUGCUCAUGGAGUCUGUGCAGGGGCCAGCAGAGGAGGACACUGCUAGCCCCUUGGCUUUGCUGGAAGAGCUGACCUUGGGGGACUGCCGCCAGGACCUUGCCACCAAGCUGGUGAAACUCUUUCUUGGCCGGGGACUGGCUGGGCGCUUUCUGGACUAUCUCACCCGGCGUGAGGUGGCUCGGACCAUGGACCCCAACACCCUCUUCCGUUCUAACUCCCUGGCAUCCAAGUCGAUGGAACAGUUUAUGAAGCUCGUGGGCAUGCCCUACCUGCACGAGGUCCUGAAGCCUGUGAUUAGCCGUGUCUUUGAGGAGAAGAAGUACAUGGAGCUGGAUCCCUGCAAGAUGGACCUGGGCCGCACCCGGAGGAUCUCCUUCAAAGGCGCACUCUCGGAGGAGCAGAUGCGGGAGACCAGCCUGGGGCUGCUGACGGGCUACCUGGGGCCCAUCGUGGACGCCAUCGUGGGCUCCGUGGGGCGCUGCCCGCCCGCCAUGCGCCUCGCCUUCAAGCAGCUGCACCGGCGAGUGGAGGAGCGCUUCCCCCAGGCCGAGCACCAGGAUGUGAAGUACCUGGCCAUCAGUGGAUUUCUCUUCUUGCGAUUCUUCGCACCUGCCAUCCUUACCCCAAAGCUGUUUGACCUUCGGGACCAACACGCGGACCCCCAGACUAGCCGCUCACUGCUGUUGCUUGCCAAGGCUGUGCAGAGCAUUGGAAACCUGGGCCAGCAGCUGGGCCAAGGCAAGGAACUGUGGAUGGCCCCCCUGCACCCCUUCCUGCUGCAGUGUGUCUCACGUGUGAGAGACUUCCUGGACCGGCUGGUGGAUGUGGAUGGGGAUGAAGAAGCUGGUGUCCCAGCCAGGGCCCUGUUCCCGCCCUCGGCCAUUGUUCGAGAAGGCUAUCUGCUGAAGCGCAAGGAGGAGCCUGCCGGCCUGGCCACGCGCUUUGCCUUCAAGAAGCGCUACGUCUGGCUCAGCGGGGAGACCCUCUCCUUCUCCAAGAGUCCUGAGUGGCAGAUGUGUCACUCCAUCCCCGUGUCUCACAUCCGCGCCGUGGAGCGCGUAGACGAGGGCGCCUUCCAACUGCCCCACGUGAUGCAGGUGGUGACGCAGGACGGCACGGGGGCGCUGCACACCACCUACCUCCAGUGCAAGAAUGUGAAUGAGCUCAACCAGUGGCUCUCGGCCUUGCGCAAGGCCAGCGCCCCCAACCCGAACAAGCUGGCCGCCUGCCACCCCGGUGCCUUCCGCAGCGCGCGCUGGACCUGCUGCCUCCAGGCUGAGCGCUCAGUGCCAAGAUGAGACGUUUGAGAUUCCAGUGGAUGCCUCUGACCCAGCCUCAGGAUGGGGACUCAAGGAGGGCUUCCUGGAGGAGGUGCUGCUUAAAUGUGACCUGAGUAGAGCAGAAGUUAAGCAGCGGCAUUGGAGACAGAACUGGGAGAUGGGGGUAAGGAAGUGUUGCAGGUGUCAUGAGCAAAGGCCUAGAGGUUGGGACAAGGUAGGCUGACGGAUGGAAAAGGGUCUGUGUGACUGGAGCCUAGAAUGAGGGAGGAGUACCGGGAGAGGCGAGGCUACUGCUAGAGUCUGGGGAGCAGAAGUGGGGCUGGAUGAGAGUGGAGGAUGUAAGAUUCAACGGAAGUAGUGGGUUUUUUUAUUUUUGUUUUUGAGACAGAGUCUCUGUUGCCCAGGCUGGAGUGCAGUGGUGCAAUCAUGGCUCCCUGCAGCCUCAAACUCCUGGGCUCAAGCAGUCCUCUCACCUCAGCCUCCCAAGUAGCUGGGACCACAGACGUGCCACCAUGUGAGGCUAAUAUUUUUGUGUGUGUGUGAGAUGGAGUCUCACCCUUUUGCCCAGGCUAGAAUGCACUGGUGCAAUCUUAGCUCACUGCAAUCUGUGCCUCCCAGGUUCAAGAGAUUCUCCUGCCUCAGCCUCCCAAGUAGCUGAGAUUACAGGCAUGAGCCACCACGCCUGGCUAAUUUUUGUAUUUUUAGUAGAGAUGGGAUUUCACCACAUUGGCCAGGCUGGUCUGAAACUCCUGACCUCAGGUGAUCCACCCACCUUGGCCUCCCAAAGUUCUGGGAUUACAGGCGUGAGCCACCGCUCCAGACCCAAGGGUAAUUUUUAAAUUAUUUGUAGAGACAAGGUCUCACUAUGUUGCCCAGGCUGGUCUUGAACUCUUGGGCUCGAGUGAUCCUCCCAUCUCAGCCUCCAAAAGUGCUGAGAUUACAGGCAUGAGCCACCGUGUGUGGCCUAGAAGUAGUAGGUUUGAGGAGGGAUUUUACAGGAAGAAGGAGCACGGCUUGGCGAAUGCCUGGCUGUGGAGGCUUCUGGAAGGGGAGAGGGAGUUACUGAUGAAUGAAGCUGUGUUCCCUCAGCCGCCGGCUGCAGCCGUACACACUCAGCUGUCACCCUGGGGGACUGGAGUGACCCACUGGAUCCUGAUGCUGAGGCCCAGACAGUGUAUCGGCAGCUGCUCCUGGGGCGGGACCAG